GUUCUGGAGACUCAACAUGAAGCUACCGGCCAGGGUUUUCUUUACUCUGGGGUCCCGGCUGCCCUGUGGCCUCGCUCCUCGGAGGGUAAGGCGGCCGGGGGCGCGGGGAGCGAGGACAGGGCGUCUCGACGCGCAAAGAGAGAGGACAGGGCGUCACGGGGGCUCGGGGAGCGAGGACAAGGCAUCCUGGGGCGCAAAGAGAGAGGACAGGGCGUCCCGGGGGUUCGGGGAGCGAGGACAGGGCAUCCCGAGGCGCAGAGAGAGAGAGGACAGGGCGUCCCGGGGCCUCGGGGAGCGAGGACAGGGUGUCCCGGGGCUCAAAGAGAGAGGACAGGGCGUUCUGGAGCGCUAAGAGAGCACAGAGCAACCCGGGGAGCGAGAGAGAGGACAGGACGUCUCGGGGCGCAAGAGAAAGGGCAGGAAGUCUUGGGGCACAAAGAGAGGACCCGGCGUCCCUGGGGCUCAGGGAGCUAGGACAGGGCGUUUUGGGGCGCAGAGAGAGAGGACCACCAGGUCCCGGAGCGAAGGGCAACGCCGGGAGUGAGCACCGGGGCCCGGGUCGUAUUCCACUGUCAGAUGAAGCCCUGAUGUGUGUAGGGGAAUAGGGAAGAGACGUGAUUUUCGAAGUUUUCACAGUUCUGCAAGUUUCCAACUUGUGUGUAAAUAGGUAGAAAGAGGUAGGGAAGGAUACGGCGCCCGUCCACCCCUUAAGGAGUGAGAGGGGAUCAGGCCGAGCGAGCACUGACCUUUGACGUCCUUUGUUGUGAGGAAAGUCCAUCUAUGUGUUAGUUAUGGAAUUAAACACUAAUACAAACAAAUUAUCAUAAAAAUGAAACAAAAACAAAACCCCAGCUGUUUAUAGACUCCCCUUCCCAGAUGUAUAGCUGGGAGAGGUCCGUCUCACACUGGCUUCCCCCUCUCUCUGGCCCACACUCCUGUCACCAUCUCCAUUGCACCCAUAGUGGAAAUAGCUAGGAAGUGAAAACAGCUAGGAAGAAGAAAGAGAAACAAAAACAAAAAGAAGCAAUAAUAUCCAAGACAAGCCCUCCCCACAUCUAAAUUACAAAAUUGUUAUAAGUAAACUAAAAAGCACAUUUUCUUUAGCCAGGUAGAAAAAUUAAUAUGUCAACUGUGAAAAAACUUCUUUUGAUUUGAUAGAAUAGACAGCCAUGGUGUUGUUUUUCAAAAAAUAUGGGCAGCAGUAGUUCCAAAUAGGAAUACAAAGAAUUAGUAUGGUGGUUCCCUCAAGUAAGGUAUCUUUCUUUUAAAAAGUGAGAUUUGUUCAGGGUUAGGGUUUUGCUGAUUUUUUUUCUCUCCCUGUGAAAACUGGGUUAUAGAUCAUUAUAAAGGAAGCCCAUAUUUUCUGAUACUUUUCAGAGACAUUUCUCAUUUGAAAUCUACAACAGCUCUGUGAUGUCUUCAGAGAUUUCAUUUUUUAACACACAUCAUUAGGAUUGUAGCAAUAAGGUCAUACAGACCUUAUCCAAGCUCUUCUGACACCAUUAGACAAUACAGUUUGAGAAGGAGAAAAUGAACUCAUUUAAAAAUUAAUUGUAAUCUGACAAUUUUGAAAUUCCUUUGCUGAAGAAAAAUAUGGAAGUUUUGAGGUUCAGGGUUGGGAGGCAAGAGAGGUACCUGUUAGUGUGGUUUGUCCCCUUCCUAGCACAUGUAGCCUCAAGUUUGAAUUCCUGGGAGAAGAAAAGUCUUUACAUCUGUGAUGUGGGAGGUUGUUCCAGGGAACAUCAUGUUUUUGUGGGCAAAUACAAGUUGUUAUAAUUAAAACCCCUAAUUUGAAUAUUUUUGUUACCAAGAACCAAGGCAAAUGUUUAAUUUGUUAUAAAACCUGUUUGUGAAGUGCUGUGUUAAAUUGUGCUGCUGGCUAAUAGGCCUCAUUUCAAUUUAAUAAAUAUUUAUUGAGGACUGGCUUUAUGUCUGGCCCUGUGCUAUGCCCUGGGACUCAAAAUUUAAAAAAUACGAGCCCUGCUCUCAACUGUUCUCAAGUUGCUCUCAGUUCUAUUGAGGAAAACAUUCAGUCAUUCAGUUGUUUAUGAGGAAACACUAAUUAAUUAAGUACCUAUUAAGUAUUGGGCAUUCUUUGGCAAUUUGUGGUUGAAAGACAUUCCUGCCUUCAAUGUACUAUAGUCUCAUAUAUGUAUUUUAAGCCACAAAUAAUAACCAAUGAGUAGGCCUUGAAAUCAAUUUAGUGGAGCAAAACAGCACUUUGGGAGGCUGAGGCGGGUGGAUCAUUAGAUCAAGAGAUCAAGACUAUCCUGGCCAACAUGGUGAAACCCUGUCUCUAGUAAAAAUACAAAAAUUACUGGGUGUGGUUUCACACGCCUGUAGUCCCAGCUACUUGGGAGGCUGAGGCAGGAGAAUCGCUUUAACCUGGGAGGCAGAGGUUGCAGUGAGCUGAGGUCGCGCCACUGUAGUCCAACCUGGCGAUAGAGUGAGUGAGACUCCAUCUCAAAAACAAAAAAAUGGAAUAGAAUAGGAUAUAUCUAAAUUCAUCUCAUGUAGUAAGGUUGUUCAUUUUGUGAAACUUUAAAAAAAAAAUUUACCAUUCUUCCUUUUUUGAUUCAUUCUUUGAUUACUAUCAUGCACACUGCCAUGUUUCUUUUCCUUUUGUUUUUAUCAAGAGUAAUAACUAUCCAACCUGAUCAACAUGGUGAAACCCUGUCUCUACUGAAAAUAUAAAAAUUAGCCGGGCGUGGUGGCGCGUGCCUGUAAUCCCAGCUACUCAGGAGGCUGAGGCAGGAGCUACUCAGGAGGCUGAGGCAGGAGAAUCACUUGAACCUAGGAGGCAGAGGUUGCAGUGAGCCAAGAUCACGCCAUUGCACUCCAGCCUGGGCAACAAAGUGAGAUUCUAUCUCAAAAAGAAAAAAAAAAAAAAGAAUAGUAACUAUCAAGAGUAAAAUCACUAUUUUUAGAAAAAUGAUUCCUGGCCAAUAUUCAGCAAUACAGUUAACAAAGUAAGAUAUGACCUCAAACUGGCCACCUAGAAUUAACUUGGGUUAGCAUUUGGUGUAUAUCAUUCCAGGCAUCUGUUCUGGUAAAAGGAUGGAUAGGCAUAAUUUUACUUGGAUGUCACAUUUUCCCUUAGUCAACAUUGUUUCAUUGUUUUCUCACGAUGAAUAUUGUCUUGGAGCAGUAUAAAACCAACUAGAUGUGUUUUCUUUAUUUUUUUUAAAUCUGGAAGCCUAAGUAUUUCUUUAUUCAGUGUAAAAUUCUGGAAUAUAAGCUCUAUGCAGGCAAAGAUUUUCAACUGUUUUGUCCACUGUUUAUACCUAGAACAGUGCUUAGCAUAGAGUAAACAUGUAACAAAUAUCUGUUACAUGAAUGAACGUGUGUACUGUGUUGCUAUGAACAUGUGUAUGUUGCUAUAUAAAUCACAUUUCUUGCUAUGGUUCACAGUCAGAAAAAUCUGAAAAAUGAUAGUCUAGUGAGUCACCAGCAGACAUCAAUAGACUGUGAAGAUGCAGAUGUGUAUUAUAAUGCAUAUAUGACCCAAACUGUACAUACCUAGAGGAGGCAAGGAAAGCUUCAUGGAGGAGGUGGCCCCAGGAGCCUGCUGUUAAAUCAGGAGUUGGAAUUUGUGUGGUCCCAAUGGCAAUAUAGACCUAAGGAAUAGCAUGUAUCAAGAAGUGAAAGAGUGGCUUAUUUAUAAAAAUUCAAGUGGUUUGUUUGGUAUUGUGGAGUUGGUGAAGUAUGGGAACAGAGAGAAGCGUGUGGAGACGAGAUCAGUCAGGUUGCUGGGGGACAGGGUAUGGUGGGCUUUUCUUAUUUAUGUAGAAAAUUGAGCAUUUACUAUUUGCUAGGCACCUUACUAGGGAUAUGAAGGUGAGAAGAAGAGCUGAUUCCUGCUGUCAAGAAGCAUAGAGUCCAAUGGCAUUAUGGUGAUGAACAGCCUCCUUCUAAAUCAUUGACCACAUUUCUUAUUCUUUCCUGAGGAUAAAUUUCAAGAUAUCCUGAACCAACUGAUGACAGCCUAUUUAGCUACAGGAAUACUCUGGAAGGAAAUGUUUUUCAGUUAUGGGACAAAAAUAUUAUAUCAAAACACUGAAGCUUUGCAAUCUAAAUUCUUUUCACCUCUUCAAAAAGCGAUGCUACCACCUAAUAGUUUUCAAGGAAAAGUGGCAUUCAUUACUGGGGGAGGUACUGGCCUUGGUAAAGGAAUGACAACUCUUCUGUCCAGCCUAGGUGCUCAGUGCGUGAUAGCCAGCCGGAAGAUGGAUGUUUUGAAAGCUACCGCAGAACAAAUUUCUUCUCAAACUGGAAAUAAGGUUCAUGCAAUUCAGUGUGAUGUGAGGGAUCCUGAUAUGGUUCAAAACACUGUGUCAGAACUGAUCAAAGUUGCAGGACAUCCUAAUAUUGUGAUAAACAAUGCAGCAGGGAAUUUUAUUUCUCCUACUGAAAGACUUUCUCCUAAUGCUUGGAAAACCAUAACUGACAUAGUUCUAAAUGGCACAGCCUUCGUGACACUAGAAAUUGGAAAACAACUAAUUAAAGCACAGAAAGGAGCAGCAUUUCUUUCUAUUACUACUAUCUAUGCUGAGACUGGUUCAGGUUUUGUAGUACCAAGUGCUUCUGCCAAAGCAGGUGUGGAAGCCAUGAGCAAGUCUCUUGCAGCUGAAUGGGGUAAAUAUGGAAUGCGAUUCAAUGUGAUUCAACCAGGGCCUAUAAAAACCAAAGGUGCCUUUAGCCGUCUGGACCCAACUGGAACAUUUGAGAAAGAAAUGAUUGGCAGAAUUCCCUGUGGUCGCCUGGGGACUGUAGAAGAACUCGCAAAUCUUGCUGCUUUCCUUUGUAGUGAUUAUGCUUCUUGGAUUAAUGGAGCAGUCAUUAAAUUUGACGGUGGAGAGGAAGUACUUAUUUCAGGGGAAUUCAACGACCUGAGAAAGGUCACCAAGGAGCAGUGGGACACCAUAGAAGAACUCAUCAGGAAGACAAAAGGUUCCUAAGACCACUUUGGCCUUCAUCUUGGUUACAGAAAAGGGAAUAGAAAUGAAACAAAUUAUCUCUCAUCUUUUGACUAUUUCAAGUCUAAUAAAUUCUUAAUUAACAAACAUUCAUUGAAUAUGUAUUAUGUGCCAGGCCAGUGAUAGCCAUUGUAUAUUCAAAGAUAAAUAAAAUGAAAUAUAGUCCUUCAAAACAUUAAAAAAAAAAAAAGGAGGCAUGGGGAGAGUAGGUAAAGGCUCCUCUUUACCUAUUGAUAGAGGUAAAAAGUACUUAGAAGUGCAGAGAGAACAGAUCUUUGUGACUUGGAAAAUCAGGAGAAACUCAAUGGUGGCGGUAGCAUUUGAGUUACAUAAUAUACUAUACCUAUAUUAAUAGGGCCUAAAAGAAAGAAAUUAGAGGAUACACACUAAAUAUAAUAGACUUUGCCUUUCCAGUAUACUUUCUUUUCACUGGACUUGUGAAUUAUCUUCUUUGGGUAACUCAGUAUUAACUCAAACCUUUAAUUUUUACUAGGACCUAUUUGUAGCCAGGCAUUUUAUUUAGUACUGAAUAAGCUAUAGCCGUUGCCCUUUUUAAAUUCAUUAUCUAGCAAGAUAGUCAAACUUAUAAAUAAUUAUUUAUGAUACAUUGUGAUAAGUAUUAUUCCAGCAGUAUUUAAGUGUAGAGGAGGAAGUAAUUCAUUCUGUCUCCAGAGUUUGGAGAAUGUGAUGCCUAAGAGAUAGCAUGCCAUCCCAGCUGUAAAAGAAGAAUAGAUUUCUCUGGGUAAAAGAGGUAAAGAAAGCCUAUAAAAUAUUUUUGUAUAUCAUUUGAUUAAAUUUCAUCUUUGGUUUGACUAAUUUGUCAUCCUGAAAAUCAAAUAAUAAUGAAUCCAAAGUCUCAAGUCUACAGAGCUAUACUUUUGAGCCUAUAUUUUUAAAAUGUCCAUUUUGCUUUCCCAGGAGUCAGUUACAACAUGUUCACUAGACUGACUAUCCCCAUUGCCCAAGUUGACACAAGAGGAAACCAGCUUCCAUCUUACCUCAUCUGAAUAAAUCUGCCACAAGCCCAUGGAAACCCCAAUUAACAUUGACAGUUAAUUGUGUACAUAAAUUACAUUUAUUACAUUUAAUUGUGUAUAUAUAGGGGAUGUUAUAGGUUUGGAAUAAGUGGCCCAACAUUUCCAAUUAUACUGACUUUCACUGGGCUUUUUUUUAGGCUGUUGCACUUUUUCUCCACAUGCUUGCAAUACAAUACUCUCAAAAUAAAACGCAGACAGGUACCUAGUCUCCAUUUUACCUUUAGUACUAAUCCUGUGUAUUAGUCUGUUCUCAUGCUGCUAAUAAAGACAUAACCCAAACUGGGUAAUUUAUAAAAGAAAGAGGUUUCAUUGACUCAUAGUUCAGCAUGGCUAGGGAGGCCUCACAAUCAUGGCAGAAGGUGAGUGAGGAGCAAAGUCAUGUCUUACGUGGUGGCACCCAAGAGAGCUUGUGCAGGGGAACUCCCAUUUAUAAAACCAUCAGAUCUCGUGAGACUUAUUCACUAUCACACUAUUGUGUUGAUAUUGUGUUCACACACCAAUAAUGAUGGUUUAUCACUCACUCCAUUUCCAAACCCACCUUCCCACCCACCUCUCACCAAACACACAAAGACACACUCUUUCCCUCCACUGAUUCCACCAGUAUAGCCAUAUUUCUCUUUCUGGUUAAAUUUAUACUAAAUGUUUACAUUUAUAUAACUUAAUAAAUAUUAUUUUUUUCCA